UUUUUUUUUUUUUUUGAGACAGAGUCUUGCUCUGUUGCCCAAGCCGUAGAGCAGUGGCGCGACCUCGGCUCACUGCAACCUCCGCCUCCCGGGUUCAAGCAAUUCUCCUGCCUCGUCCUCUCGAGUAGCUGGGACUACAGGUGCACGCCACCAUGCCCAGCUAAUUUUUUUGUAUUUUUAGUAGAGACAGGUUUCACCAUGUUGGCCAGGAUGGUCUCAAUCUCUUGACCUUGUGAUCCGCCCGCCUCGGCCUCCCAAAGUUCUGGGAUUAUAGGCAUGAACCACCGCGCCCAGCCUGGAGUAGACUUUUUGCUCCAAGUGAGAUGGGGAGACACUGCAGGGUUCAGAGCCAACAAGGAGUAACAUAUACAGUUCCUGAGUUCUACCUUCCCAUGGGGACCCAGGUGUCAUAUCUGGUUUUCUUUUUUUUUCUUUUUUAGAGACAGUGUCACUCUAUUGCCCAGGCUGGUCUCGAACUCCUGGGCUCAAGAAAUCCUCCCGCCUCAACCUCCCAAAGUGCUGGGGCUACAGGUGUGAGCCACCAUGCCUGACUGGUGUCAUAUUGAUGCAGCUCUUAACAACCACCUGCCCAGCCACCCUUCUGGCUUCUCUCUUUUCAUACCUCAGUUCAUUAGGGGACUCAGGGAUGUACGGCUGACCCCAAGUCUUCCCAAACAGAUGCCAGGGAAGGCCUGAGUAGAUCAUUUGGACCUUUCCAAGUAGUUCAUAUGGAAUCCUCCUGCUGUCUCCCUAAUCCCUUUGGCUCCUAGACUUAAUCCCACCCUGCCCCUUCCCCCUGAGCUUCUUAAUAGGGCAAAGGGGAAGGGUAGAAAGGCAGUGAGAACAGCUGGGACUCGCCUGCUCUUGGGACAGUGUGAUUACCAAGGGUUUUCUGUGCCCUGUCUGGUAUUUUGUCUCUGUGCCUGUCCCUUUGGGCACACUGUGGACCCCCACCCCAGGUUUGUGUGGACUUUCCUUUCUGCCCUUGUCAUCUCCCCCAGCCUUCAGGGUGUCAGCGGCUCAUCUUUCCCCUGUGUGUUGCUGGAGUCUCUUGGUUCCUCUCGGCCUUUCUGUUCAUCUCCCAUCUCUUCCUAGGCCCUAGACUCCCUUUGCUAUGGAUAGGAGAGGAAUGAGGAGAGUAGGAGGGAACAGGUGCCCAGGGUCCUGGGUUUUGCAUAGGACAGCAAGGGGCUGUGGGUAUGAAAACCUUGCUUUUGUCUGAGACUCGCUCCCCAGCCAGUUCUUUCCCCACUGGCCAGUCUGCUGGGCUCCUCUGGGAAGUUCACUCGAUUGCCCCCAAGGUGCCCAAAGACUCGGUUCUGAUCACAAGACUUAUCGCCAUGUAUUUUAAUUUCUUUUUACCCCUCUGCCUCCCACACUCGAAAUAGCAGGGACCUUGGUCUUAUAUUAUUCACUUCUGCCUCCCAAGCCCCUGCCAACGUACAGGGCAAAGUCUGAUGUUUUGAAAUGAUAUGAUCGAAGAGGGAAACUCUAGAAUUGGAGAGCCAGUAUGGAAAGGAAAACUGGAUCCCAGAGUGGAUGGGGAGAGUGAGUGGGGCACCUGAGUCCAGCCCCCACCCCCACGUUCCGCCAGUCCCACCUGCUCCCUUGCAGACUCCGCCCCCCCCGCCCCCGCUUUCUCUCCCUCAACCCCCGCGGGCUUCUCCCCUGCUGACCUUGCCUCCUGCCCCCUUUUUCUCCCUCCUUCAGCUUAAGAUCUCCUUCAGCGAGACAGCCCUGGAGACCACGUACCAAUACCCCUCCGAGAGUUCGGUACUGGAGGAGCUGGGCCCGGAGCCUGAGGUCCCCAGUGCCCCCAACCCUCCAGCAGCCCAACCCGACGACGAAGAGGAUGAGGAAGAGCUGCUGCUGCUGCAGCCAGAGCUCCAGGGCGGGCUGCGCACCAAGGCCCUGAUUGUGGAUGAGUCCUGCCGGCGGUGACCAUCUUCCAACAUAGGGAUAUACCUCCCUCCUUCUUAUAACUGAAGAUCCUGGAGCCCGGAAGAUUCAGGGCAGACAGACCCUGAUAAUGAGCCUGGCAGGGAAGGGCAACCAACAUCUUGUAACUUGCUUUCCCCACCCUGUUUCUGGGGGCAGAGCCAAUUGCCCAAUUUCUACCCUAAUCCAAAGUCCCUGGUGUGGGUGGGGUUAAACGUGCUGGUGCAUCCUAGGUCAUCCAAGAGUGAGCGCCAAGUCCUGAGAAGGGGCACAGAACUCCCUGGAGGGUGGAGAUGGAGCACCUGCCCCCCAUGGCAGGGUACACUCUCCCCACAGCCUUCCUCCCCACCAUCCCGUGGGGACUCUCGGGAUUUAAGCACUCGUCUCUCUGGGAGGCCCAGACCCCACUCCAUUUAUAGGCACAUCUCCUUCAUUUCCUAGGUCACUGCCCCUUUGUUUACAGCUCCUGCCUCCUCCCUUGACCACAGCCUGGUUUACAAAUUCCAUCAGCUCCCAGCCCCACCUGCCAAAGUCCCAGGUUUACAAGCCACGCUUACUUGCUGUGUCUGCGUGGAAUUCUCUCCUCUGUCCCCUCCAGUCUCCUCAUUGGAGUGACCUGAAGGUGUGGCUUCCUCCACUUUUUCUCAGUAUUACUUUGCCUUAGUUUUCCCCAAGAGGGAAGGCUGGAACUCUUAACUCUGUACCCCUUGAUAGUUAUUUAAUUCUGUUUCUCCUAGUGGUUCACAAUUGAACUGAAUUGAGAUGGUGUCGGGUGGCUAAGGAGACACCUCACCUCUCCUUCCCCAUUGUGCCGCCUUUAUCAAUUGCCUGUUUUGUUUUGUUUGUUUUUUAACUUUCCAUAAUAAAAUGGAGUUCUCUUCAA